AGACGGUGCCGACGCAGCGGUGUUGCACCUCCCUCUCCGGCUCUGCUGCCCGGGAUUUCCCCAGAACCUGCGCCGCGCGAGAAGGAGCCUGGGAGCAUCCGCCCACACUGCCCGGACAGUCGGCUCGACUCGGUGCCCUCGGCCCCAGCCGGGCUCCGCUCCUCGGGCGCGCGAGGGGCCGUGGUGGCGGCGGCGCCCGGCAUGUUUCAUAGUCCGCGGCGGCUCUGCUCGGCCCUGCUGCAGAGGGACGCGCCCGGCCUGCGCCGCCUGCCCGCCCCAGGGCUGCGCCGCCCGUUGUCCCCGCCGGCUGCUGUUCCCAGGCCCGCAUCCCCCCGGCUGCUGGCGGCGGCCUCGGCGGCCUCGGGCGCCGCGAGGUCGUGUUCCCGAACAGUGUGUUCCAUGGGAACCGGUACAAGCAGACUCUAUAGUGCUCUCGCCAAGACACUGAACAGCAGCGCUGCCUCCCAGCACCCAGAGUAUUUGGUGUCACCUGACCCAGAGCAUCUGGAGCCCAUUGAUCCUAAAGAGCUUCUUGAGGAAUGCAGGGCCGUCCUGCACACCCGACCUCCCCGGUUCCAGAGGGAUUUUGUGGAUCUGAGGACAGAUUGCCCUAGUACCCACCCACCUAUCAGGGUUAUGCAAUGGAACAUCCUCGCCCAAGCUCUUGGAGAAGGCAAAGACAACUUUGUACAGUGCCCUGUUGAAGCACUCAAAUGGGAAGAAAGGAAAUGUCUCAUCCUGGAAGAAAUCCUGGCCUACCAGCCUGAUAUAUUGUGCCUCCAAGAGGUGGACCACUAUUUUGACACCUUCCAGCCACUCCUCAGUAGACUAGGCUAUCAAGGCACGUUUUUCCCCAAACCCUGGUCACCUUGUCUAGAUGUAGAACACAACAAUGGACCAGAUGGUUGUGCCUUAUUUUUUCUUCAAAACCGAUUCAAGCUAGUCAACAGUGCCAAUAUUAGGCUGACAGCCAUGACAUUGAAAACCAACCAGGUGGCCAUUGCACAGACCCUGGAGUGCAAGGAGUCAGGCCGACAGUUCUGCAUCGCUGUUACCCAUCUAAAAGCACGCACUGGCUGGGAGCGGUUUCGAUCAGCUCAAGGCUGUGACCUCCUUCAGAACCUGCAAAACAUCACCCAAGGAGCCAAGAUUCCCCUUAUUGUGUGUGGGGACUUCAAUGCAGAGCCAACAGAAGAGGUCUACAAACACUUUGCUUCCUCCAGCCUCAACCUGAACAGCGCCUACAAGCUGCUGAGUGCUGAUGGGCAGUCAGAACCCCCAUACACUACCUGGAAGAUCCGGACCUCAGGGGAGUGCAGGCACACCCUGGAUUACAUCUGGUAUUCUAAACAUGCUCUAAAUGUAAGGUCAGCUCUCGAUCUGCUCACUGAAGAACAGAUUGGACCCAACAGGUUACCUUCCUUCAAUUAUCCUUCAGACCACCUGUCUCUAGUGUGUGACUUCAGCUUUACUGAGGAAUCUGAUGGACUUUCAUAAAUACUUGCUUUUGUCUUUUUAAUCACAGGAGUCUAUUUUUUUUUUUUUUUUUUUUUUUUUGAGACAGAGUCUCGCUCUGUUGCCUAGGCUGGAGUACAGUGGCCUGAUCUCGGCUCACUGCAAGAUCCGCCUCCCGGGUUCAUGGCAUUCUCCUGCCUCAGCCUCCAGAGCAACUGGGACAACAGGCGCCCGUCACCACGCCCAGCUAAUUUUUUGUAUUUUUAGUAGAGACGGGGUUUCACCGUGUUAGCCAGGAUGGUCUCGAUCUCCUGACCUUGAAUCACAAGAGUCUUAACAGGGAAUGUUUCAGGAAACAAAUAGGAUAAGACAAUGCCAGAGGAAGGAUAGAAACAUGGGAAGUUUCUAUCAUUUCAUUUUCUGCGUUUCCAGCAUGCCCUUGGAAAAGACUCCCUUUAGUCCCUUUUUCAAUUAAAACCUAUGGUGAAAAAGGCGUUUGCACUCCAA